ACACUGCUGGCCGGCUCUGUUCAAGUGUGGGAGGUCAGGAGCAGCCAGUUCCUCCUGGGAAUGCAACCCAUCUCCGAAAAGGAUUAAGCAUCACUAGGGCUCCAAGUGAGUUCUGAUCAGAGGCUGUUCGGAAGACAGCAGGGGCCAUGACCACCCUCUCUCCUGAAAACAGCCUCUCUGCCAGACAGUCAGCCUCCUUCAUCCUGGUGAAGAGAAAACCACCCAUUGACAAGACAGAAUGGGACAGCUUCUUUGAUGAGAGUGGCCACUUGGCCAAAUCACGGGACUUCAUUUGUGUUAACAUCCUGGAAAGGGGUCUGCACCCCUUCGUGAGGACUGAAGCCUGGAAAUUCCUCACGGGCUACUUCUCAUGGCAGAGUUCCCAGGAUGAGCGGCUCACGGUGGACAGCAUGAGGAGGAAGAACUACAAGGCCUUAUGCCAAAUGUAUGAGAAGAUUCAGCCCCUUCUGGAAAACCUGCACCGGAACUUCACAGAGACUCGCAAUAACAUUGCACGUGACAUUCAGAAAAUCUAUGACAAAGAUCCCCUGGGCAACGUCCUCAUCGACAAGAAGAGGCUAGAGAAGAUCCUGCUCCUGAGUUACGUCUGCAACACGCAGGCAGAGUACCAGCAGGGCUUCCAUGAGAUGAUGAUGCUCUUCCAGCUGAUGGUGGAGCACGACCACGAGACCUUCUGGCUUUUCCAGUUCUUCCUGCAGAAAACGGAACACAGCUGUGUCAUCAACAUUGGCGUGGCCAAGAACCUAGACAUGCUCAGCACCCUGAUCACCUUCCUGGACCCCGUGUUUGCUGAGCACCUAAAAGGGAAGGGUGCAGGGGCUGUGCAGUCCCUCUUCCCCUGGUUCUGCUUCUGCUUCCAGCGUGCCUUCAAGUCCUUCGAUGAUGUCUGGAGGCUCUGGGAGGUUCUGCUGACGGGGAAGCCCUGCAGGAACUUCCAGGUGCUGGUGGCCUACAGCAUGCUGCAGAUGGUGCGGGAGCAGGUGCUGCAGGAAAGCAUGGGCGGGGAUGACAUCCUCCUGGCCUGCAACAACCUCAUCGACCUUGAUGCUGAUGAGCUGAUCUCUGCCGCCUGCGUGGUUUAUGCUGAGCUCAUCCAGAAGGAUGGUGGCAUAGCCCUGUUCCUCUGCAGGACUCAUCACAGCCAGGGAGGCCCCUCUUCUGGUGUUUUCAGACUCAAGGACACCGAGACUCACUUCUUUCUCAUGACAUAACCUCCAAGUUACAACACUCAGAAGCUGUCAGUGGUCAUAUUUUCUGUCUUAGACAAAACCAGUCUUCUGGGAAAAGAACAAAUGAGGCUGAUCUGCAGCAAGAAGCAAAAACAAGAACCUGGUGGGGCUGCUGUGGCUUGCAAAUCCCUGGUUCCAGAUGUCUCUAAGGCCCACCCACAUCCCCGCCCCUCUGCUGGCUCAAUUAUUGGGCUGUUUCUUAGAUUCUGUGAGAUGCUCCAAGAUCCUCCAAUAAAUCCUCAUUUUUG